ACUGUGCAGCCCAGGCGCCGGGCGCUGCCUCUACAGCUGUGUGUAGGCCUGGGGGCGAGGGUCUUCGGAACGUAGCGCUGGCUGCGGCCCCGCCCGCCUACCCACCCGCCCGUCCGGCAGCCGGCUCCCGCCGCCUCCGCGCUCUGUCUGGGGCCAGCCACCUGGCGGGCCGCUCCGGUGCGCCUGCCCGCGCUUUUCACUGACAGGCGCUGUUCCCCACAGCCAGCGCCGCCCGCCACGUCCCAGCUCUCGGCCAACGGAGCUGCGCGGCGGGUGACCUUUCCGAGCCCAGCGCGAUGACGGCUCCUUGCUCCCAGCCGGCGCAGCUUCCUGGACGCCGCCAGCUCGGGCUGGUGCCGUUCCCGCCGCCGCCGCCGCGGACGCCGCUGCUGUGGCUGCUGCUGCUGCUGCUGGCCGCCGUGGCGCCGGCGCGCGGCUGGGAGAGCGGAGACCUGGAGUUGUUUGACUUAGUGGAGGAGGUGCAGCUCAACUUCUACCAGUUCCUCGGGGUGCAGCAGGAUGCAUCAUCUGCAGACAUCAGAAAAGCAUAUCGUAAGCUUUCACUAACUUUACAUCCAGACAAGAAUAAAGAUGAAAAUGCAGAAACUCAGUUUAGACAAUUGGUGGCCAUUUAUGAAGUUUUAAAGGAUGAUGAACGAAGGCAGAGGUAUGAUGAUAUUCUGAUCAAUGGACUUCCAGAUUGGCGACAGCCUGUAUUCUACUACAGGCGGGUGAGAAAAAUGAGCAAUGCUGAGCUGGCAUUACUCUUGUUCAUUAUUCUCACAGUGGGUCAUUAUGCUGUGGUUUGGUCAAUCUACCUGGAAAAACAACUGGAUGAACUACUAAGUAGAAAAAAGAGAGAAAAGAAAAAAAAGACUGGCAGCAAGAGUGUGGAUGUAUCAAAACUCGGUGCUUCAGAAAAAAAUGAAAGAUUGCUGAUGAAACCACAGUGGCAUGAUUUGCUUCCAUGCAAACUGGGGAUUUGGUUUUGCCUUACACUAAAAGCAUUACCUCACCUCAUCCAGGAUGCUGGGCAGUUUUAUGCUAAAUAUAAAGAAACAAGAUUGAAGGAAAAGGAAGAUGCACUGACUAGAACUGAACUUGAAACACUUCAAAAACAGAAGAAAGUUAAAAAACCAAAACCUGAAUUUCCUGUAUACACACCUUUAGAAACUACAUAUAUUCAGUCUUAUGAUCAUGGAACUUCCAUAGAAGAAAUUGAGGAACAAAUGGAUGAUUGGUUGGAAAACAGGAACCGAACACAGAAAAAACAGGAAAUUGUCACAGACACCCCAACCUUUACCAACCACCACCCCAGUGAGUCAGCAGCCACUAACAUGAAUGCAAGACCCUCUACCAAUAGAAAGAUUAUGACUUGUUGAAAGACUCAGAUGGUUAUUAAUACGUUUUAGCGGUAAAGUAUUUUUAAAUUAUGUACAUUGUUUUUUGGACAUAAUGCUAUCACACACUUAAUAAACUAAGCUACAAUGUAAACUUAGUUUUAAACAUUUUUUUAAAUUAUUAUUAUUUUUUUGAGACAGAGUCUCUCUCUGUCGCCCAGGCUGGAGUGCAGUGGCAUGAUCUCGGCUCACUGCAACCUCUGCCUUCUGGGUUCAAGCGAUUCUUGUGUCUCAGCCUCCUGAGUAGCUGGGAUUACAGGCAAGCGCAAUCACGCCCUGCUGAUUUUUGUACUUUUGGUAGAGAUGGGGUUUCACCGUGUUGGCCAGGCUGGUCUCAAACUCUUGGCCUCAAGUGAUCCGCCUGUCUCAGCCUCCUAAAGUGCUGGGAUUAUAGGUGUGAGCUAACGCGCCUGGCUUAUAAACAACUUUUAUAUGUACUGGGAAACAAAAAAAAUUGUGUGGCUCAUUUUAUUACAAUAUUAACUUUAUUGUGGUAGCCUGGACCUGAACUUGGAAUAUCUCUGAGGUAUGCAUGUAUAGAUAUGCAGCUCAGUGAACUAUCACAGGUGAUGCAAGUUAACCAUUGCCAAGUUCAAUGACUAGAACAUUGCCAUUGUGCAGAAACCAUGCUUUCUGCCACUAUUUCCUUCUCUUCCACAAAGAUGAUGACAUUCCUGACUUCGGAGUAGUUUUACCUGCUUGUUAGUUUAUAAAUAGCAUCAUUUCCUAUGUAGUCCUUUGAGUAUGAUUUCCUCUAUUCAGUGUAUUUGUGAGAUUUAUUCAUAAUUGCAUAUAGCAGUAAUUUUCAUUGCUGUAUAAUACUUUAUAAAUAUAGCACAAUUUAUUUUUGUUGGAGAAAUGUGGUGUUUUCAGUUUGGGGCUAUAAUGAAUAAUUUUUCUGUGAACAGUCUUGUGCAUGCCUUUUAGUAUGUAUAUGUGUAAAUUUCAAUUUUUGGAGUUAGUUGCAGGGUCAGAGCUCAACUUCAGUAAAUACAGUUGAUCCUUGAAAAAUAUGGGUUUAAACUGCAUAGGUCCACUUAUAUGUGGAUUUUUUCCAAAAAAUAUUUUGGAAAAAUUUUAGAAGAUUUUGGGUAAUUGUUCAAAUCUCAAACCAUGUAGCCUAGAAAUACUGAAAAAAUUAAGAAAAAGUUAGGUAUGUCAUGCAUAAAAUGUAUGUAGAUACUAGUGUAUUUUAUCAUUUACUACCAUAAAAUAUAUACAAACCUAUCAUAAAAAGUUAAAACUUAUCAAAACAUACACAACUACUUACUGUACAUGGCACCAUUUGCAGAUGAGGGAAAUAUAAACAAAUGUAAAGAUGCAGUACUAAAUCAUAACUGUGUAAAAUCAACUGUAGCACACAGUGUACCUACUAUACUACUAUAAUAAUUUAAAACACCUCUCGUUGCUGUUGCAGUAGGCUCAUGUGUUGCAAGUGUUGGCUUAAACCUCCCGAUGAUGCUAAUCAUCUCUGUGUGAGCAGUUUGUCUCUCCAGUAAAUUGCAUAGCAUAGAAAAUGUGAUCUAUCUGGGUUCUCAUGUAUUUUUUAUCAUGUUUAGUAAAAUACUGUAAACCUUGAAUAACACCAUUGGGCCUAUGGAAAGUACCACUAGUGAUGCUAGGAGUGUUCUCGAGAACCAGAGGAAAGUCAUGACAUUACAAGAAAAAAUUGAAUUGCUUUAUAAGUAUAGUAGAGUGAGGUCUGCACCUGCUGUUGGCUGCCAUUUCAGACAGACAACAACGUGAACUUAGGGUAUUGAUAAAUACAGUACAUUACUAUAAAGGUAUUUUCCUUAAGAUUUUGUUUUCUCUAGUUUAUUGUAAGAAUGCAGUACAUAAGCAUGCAAAAUAUGUGUUAACUUAUUGUCUGCAUUAUUAAAGCUUCCAGUCAACAGUAGGCUGUUAGUAGUAAAGUUUUUGGGCAGUCAAAAGUUAUACUUAGGUUUUCAACUGACCAGGGGUUGGCGCCCCAACCUCCAUAUUGUUCAAGGGUCAGCUGUACUUUUAAAUUGUUUUCCAAAAGUUUGUGUCAAUUUAUACUUUAGCAGCAGGAUAUGAAUAUUCCAGGUACUCUAUAUUUUUGCCAAUGCUUGGUCAAGUCUUUUAUAUUUUAUCCAUUCUGGUAAGUAUGCAGUGAUACCUAAUUUUGGUCUAAUUUGCAUCCUUUGAUGAAUAAGACUGAACACCUUUUCUUAUGGUUAUUGGAUACUGAUAUCUUACUAAGUGAAGUGCCUUUCCAAAUCUUUUUUAAUUGUGUUGCCUUUUUGUUUUUAAGACUGGAUUAUAAAGAGUUCUUUCUGUAUUUCA